UCAGCCCAGUCCAGCUGAGGCUCUCGGAGGACAGGACCCGCCCCGCGCUGCCAGUGCCGAAGCUUGGGUUCUCUGAGGACUGCGAGGGGGUCUCAGCACUGUGUCCACAGAUGGGGCAGGGACCUCCGCAGGGAACCUUCUCUCGGCUGGGCCAGCCCACCCCAGGGGCUGUAGACGAGGGAGUUAAUGAACACGGGAUGGGUUGAGCCGCCUGGUUUGCCCACAGAGGGGCGAGGAAGGGAGUGGGGAGUCUGCUGUGAGCGGAGAGAGGACAGCCUGAGGCCUCAGGAACGCUGGCUGCCUGCCUGCAGCGGGAGCUAACGGGGCGUCUGUCGGGAAGGGGCACGGCCACAGGAUUUAGGGGCAGUUUGGACACACUGGUCCGGUGAGCUUGAUUUCAGAUUCCGGGAUCUGGUUUCGGAGUGGAGUUGUGGACUCUCCAGGACCCAUCGCUGAGGAGCAGGAGGUUCUCCAGGGGCCAUGGGGCCCGGGGCUCUGAGGGAGGCUCUGCACUCCCAGCAUGAGGUCACCACAGGGCUAGGCCAGGGCCCAGACACAGCAAGCCACCAAGAGGAGGCCGGCCGGCGUGGAAGCCUCGCAGAGGGUGAAUUCCAAAGAGGGCCCCUCCUGCUCUGAGACCCACACUCCCGAGCCACACUCAGCAGGUGACGUGCAACAAGACCCUUAGGGUUAGGGUUAGGGUUAGGGUUAGGGACCCCAGGCUCCAUGCAUGCCAGGGAGAGGCAGCGGUGUGCGAGGGCCUCCUGGUGCCUGGCAGACCAGGAGUGAAUUUUGGCUGUCACCUUCUCUGAGUUACUCCAGUGUAGAGAGGCAAGGCCUGGGUCCAGGGUUGUCUCAGUCUCAGUGCAGCCCCUCAGAAUGGGGGGCCCAUGCCUAGCACCCUGGGUGGGGAGGAGCAGGCAGCUAGCUGGAGCUUCUGGCCCUUUUAAAAGAGGCCCCAUUCCCUGGGCCUCGAGGGAGUGGCUGUGCACAUUCAGACAUGCACUGACCCAUGUACACACACACAUACACGCACACGUGUAUGCACACUCACACGUAUAUUUGUACAUACACAUGUGCAUACAUCCACAUGUACAGGUACACACAGGUAUGCACGAAGGAGGUUCCCAAACCCUUUCUGCACCCCUUAGCUGCCUUCCAAAGGGACACGUCCUGAUUUCCCUGUGGUGGGACACUGAGCAUGCCCAGCUUCUGCGGGGCCAGGUGACGCACACGAACUCAGGGUCUGCUGAGGCAGGUGCAUUGGCGACGGUGGACAGCAGAGAAGUGGGAUGCCUAGCGGCAGGGGCUCUGCCCUCACAGCUCCUCUGCCAGGCAGGGACCAGGUCCCGCUGUCAACCAAGGGAAGCCAGGCCCUGGCCACCCGGCCCUGCAUUUCAGAGGGGGCAGCACCCAGUGUUCUGGGGUCUCAGUUACUGAAUGAGCCUGGGCACCUGCCUGCCCUCUCUGGCCUCAGUUUACCCCCUGUACUGCUGGGCGAGGGAUCAGGGCAUAGCGAAGGACCAUUUCAGCUCCGCUGGUGCCACACUGCUGAAGUCCUGGCCGCUUUUUCCUGCAUCCUGGGGUUUUCUGACAAAAGGGGAGCAUGUUAGUGCUUGAAAUGGCCUCACCUCUUGCUAUUUUUGCAGGAAGCCUGAACGCAGUUGUUAAAAAUAGAAAUAAUGAAGGAAAGCAGCAGCUUCUGCCCUUGAGUCCUGAGGCCAGGACAGGACUCCCAGGAUCCUCUCCAGGCUUGUGAUGAUAAAUGAUCAUUGGGCUGCAUUUGUCCUUAGCUAAUUUAUCCUUGGCCUAGAGAGAAAGUUUCUGCCUUUUUUUUUUUUUAAGAGGAAAGCUGGAAAGGUGCUUGAGGCCUAAUAACUUUGCUUGGUCUUUUUUGGGCACUGGGCCCUGCAUUUUCCACCUGGCAAUGCUGUGUGGGGCUUCUUCCAGGCACUCUGUGGGCCUCAUGCCGCCUGUGCUGGCCGGAGCCAGCGUGGCGAUCAGACGUCUGGGUGUGCCCGGCACGACCCCACCUCGCCGCUCCCCUGAGCUGUCCUUCCCCUGCAGAGGGGCCAAGAAGCACCCCUGGGAGGCCAUUAGUGUCAGCAAGAAAGGUACGGCAGGGCGGGGCCAGGACAGGGUGAACAGGACCCCAGCGCUUGGUGGCCACGAGUCCCAGCUCUGGGAGGAACAGGCCUUGAGGAUGCAGAGAGGUUUGCAUUGGCAAAAGUCUCGGCAUCUCUCAUUUUUCCCGUACAUGCACCACCACCGCUGCUUCCUGCUGUAGCCCCUCUCCGCCAAGAGGCAUUCCCAGCCCCCAGGACCAUAGAGAGGGGCAGGGGUCUUCAGCGUGGCUGAGGGCCACCGCCUGCGGCACGUGGGAGGAAGCUGCCAACUACCCCCAUCCCCUGAGCUGAAGUCUCCUUGCAUCUGGGCCUUGAUUUUUUAAUGCGAGAUGCAGCUCAAGGCUUGCGGUCAUACUUCUGUCUUCAGGUGCGAAAACUGCGUUUUCUUCUUGAGUUCCGUGUUUCAGGGAGAGAAUCGUGAAGAAACAGACUAAAGGACUUUGUUGCAAGCUACAGUCAUGAAGAAGGACACGUGGGCUCUGCACCAGUCCCCGGCGCUGCCUGCGGCAUCUGAUUCUGCCGGCGCUGCCCGCUUAGCUUAUGGGUAUGCAGAAGAUCUGCAUCAUGGUUCCUGCUGAAGAAGGGAGUGUGUGGCUGUGUGUGUGUGGCUGUGUGUGUGUGCGUGUGCACAGGCAUGCACACACCUGUGUUUACAUGAACACAUAUGAAUACAGUGUAUGUGUACACACACAAACACGUGUGUGCAUGUGAGGUACAUGCAUGUGCACAUUUGCUUACAUGUACGUGUGUGUGUGCACGUGCAUACACAUGUGCGAUUGGCAAGUGUGUGCAUGCAUAUGUAUAUGGGCACAUAUAUGUACAGGCAUGUAUGCACGUUUGUGUGUUUGGUGUGUCUAUAUAUGUACGUGUAUAUGGCCACACACGGAUACAGGUAUGUAUACACCUGUGCAUGCACGCUUGCCCAGACACACAACUGCACACCUCCCUGCCCUGCACCCUGCCUUUGGGCUCUCCAUCGUUGCUGCUGGCUGAUAGGUCUUGAAAGGCCCAGGCUGGUGAGUAAGUCCUGCCCCUCAGGUGGGCAAGACUGGGAACAGCCUAUCUGGCCUUCUUCAGGUUUCCUCUCUCAGCCUGGAGGAGGGCAAUAAUGAUGCAAUUUCUUACAAUAAUGAUACCUUACAUUGCAUAAUCGUUCGGGUCACUCAAAAUAUUGAAAACAGUAGCACAGAAAGGUUAAAGGGUUCCACAGCAACUCAGCAGCACAGCCAGCACCACGAAGUCGGCCACCGCCCCACACUUUAGUCAGUUGGGUGACCUGGCCGGCCCUGGGAGGACGCCUCAUUCAGCUGAAGCUCAUCCACAUCCACGUCAGGGGGCUCCUUGGUGUCCCGGAGAUGCUGCCAGCUCCCAGCCCCAGGACGGGUGUGAGGCUGUGGCCCACGGGGGAACUCCUCCUGCACAAGGCGUCUUGGCUCCUGCCCUGCUACACCGACCACGUCCCUCCCUCAGCCGGUCCCCGAUACUGAGCACCUUAGAGGCAGCCACUCUUCGCAGGCCUGGUUACCUGUCUUGCACCAUGUGCAUCUCCUCCUGUGCAUGGAGGAGGAAACCAAGGCUUCCAGCCCCAGAGCUCGCAAAGGCAGAGACCCCAGGCUCCCUGUGUGCUCCUGUGCAUGGAGGAGGAAACCAAGGCUUCCAGCCCCGGAGCUCGCAAAGGCAGAGACCCCAGGCUCCCUGUGUGCUCCUGUGCAUGGAGGAGGAAACCAAGGCUUCCAGCCCCGGAGCUCGCAAAGGCAGAGACCCCAGGCUCCCUGUGUGCUCCUGUGCAUGGAGGAGGAAACCAAGGCUUCCAGCCCCGGAGCUCACAAACGCAGAGACCCCAGGCUCCCUCUGUGCUCCUGUGCAUGGAGGAGGAAACCAAGGCUUCCAGCCCCGGAGCUCGCAAACGCAGAGACCCCAGGCUCCCUGUGUGCUCCUGUGCAUGGAGGAGGAAACCAAGGCUUCCAGCCCCGGAGCUCGCAAAGGCAGAGACCCCAGGCUCCCUGUGUGCUCCUGUGCAUGGAGGAGGAAACCAAGGCUUCCAGCCCCAGAGCUCGCAAAGGCAGAGACCCCAGGCUCCCUGUGUGCUCCUGUGCAUGGAGGAGGAAACCAAGGCUUCCAGCCCCAGAGCUCGCAAAGGCAGAGACCCCAGGCUCCCCGUGGGCCAGGACCACUGGCCUUUCCCUCCGCUGCUUGGGGCGUCCUGCAGUACCGGGCUCAGGGAUGGAACCCUCACGCGGAGCCAGGACGAGCAGGCCACACAGAGGGAAUGCCGACCACGUCCCUGAAGCCACAGUGGUAAGAAGCUCCAUCUCCCACGGCAGAUUGCAACCGUCAGGGUUGUUAGAUUCGUGCGGACCGGACGAUGCGUCUAAAGGAAAACGGACCCAGGCAGGAACAGCAGCGGCCGCCCGAGUGUUGGCAGAAGCAGGCCUGUUGCUGAAUUGUGACGUUUGUAGAAAUCGCUGUUUUAGCCGCUGUUGGCUCCUCUCAAGCUCCUGACAGUGAUCCCAAGAUCUGCUGGGAAGCACCUUCCCCGGCGACUCCUCGGGGACACCGGCUCCAGCUGCAGCCUCAAGUGACCCCUUUGCCGGAGUCCAAGAAAAGAGAAGCUGCUUCCGUGGACUCUUCUGUCCCAGAUGAAGCCGCAGCGGCAGGAAGUGGUAGCUGGCUGCUCUCAGGGUUUAUUUGGUUGGGACAAGAGGUCCCAAAGCUGUCCUUGGGAAGGAGCUUAGGCGGGGCUGAGCUGAUGUGUGCCUCGAGGAGCGGAGGGAGAGACAGGGCAGGAGACAGGGAGAACACGGUCCAGAGGCAGCGGGGAACAGUGGGAGGGAGAGCCGGGCCCUCUGCAACGCCGGCUGUGGGCUGGGACAACAGGGGAGGGUGAGGCAGUCCCAGCUCUCAAGGCCUCUGGCCCAGGAUGAGGUGUGAGAUGGCCAAGCUGCCGUGGGGCCGCCCGGGAGGAGGAGAAGCAAACCCAUCAAGGAGGGCUCACAGGCGUGGUGAUAUCUGACGAGGCUCCUGAAGGGUGGGUAAGAGUUUUCCAGGAAGGGUGGUUGGAGGGAGCACUAGGCGAGUGGCCGGCACGAACCAAGGCCUCGGGUCCCCAGAGCCCUGUAUGGGUCGCAGUUGGGUCUUCCCAGGUUAGGGUUGAGGUUCGGGUUAUGUCUCUUCCACAGCCCUUGAGAGCAAUAGGAUUUCAGCAAAUGUAGCUUGUGUGGUUUCUGAUGGUCAGAAAUAAUCCACAUUUUAGGAUUUCUGUAAUCCUGUACUUUAAAACUGGCAUCACAGACCAUUGCCCCUGCAGACAGCAGCCUGGGCCUCCAAAUGGAGGGGCCUGCGGGGGGAUGAGCUGUCCGGAGGGUCCACACUGGAGGAGGGGGCAGGCCACGGCCCGGCUGGAGAGCCUCUGUGCCUAGUGGGCCCCGGAGCCCCAGGUCCCUGGUGCAGGGGGUGGAGGUCAGGCAGGCCCUGGGCAGCUGAUUGCUGCCUGAAGCCCACCCUGAGGAGGGAGGGAGGCAGGGGAGGAGACAGAACAGAUCCCUUGGGGGAAGCAAACCCACAUUCCCAGACCCAGGAGCGCCCACGUCAGGGGGACCCCAGGGAGGGCCAGCCCUGCGUGUACACCCCUCCUGCCAGGACCCUGCUUCGGAGGUCACACCAGCUCCUUGUGGAAUGGUCUGUUGGAGCGGACCUGACCUGGAGAAUCCACGCCUCUCACACAUGGAGCUGGGCAACAGCUGGCACCCGCCCCCUCGGCCUCAGCCUCCCUGGGGGCUCCCCCGCCACAAGAGGGGCCGUCCCGGGUGCUUUGAGUGGAGUGAGCUAGAGAGUCGGAUAUUAGGGCCACCUAGGAGAGCCGGCCUUGUCCAUCGCCUGGCCGGGGCUGGACUGACGUGAGCUGUCUCCAAGUCCAGGAGGAAACUCACAAACUCUGAGCUACACAGCAGGUAUGAGUCCUGCUGCAACACAGUGCGCUUUAAAAAGUGUGAAUAAAUUGAAACUUCAUGAAAUA